AACAGGUUGCUUCUGCAGUCUGAGCUGAGCGCCUUUCGCACGACUUGGAGUUACGGUUUAUCUGAUACCCCGGUACCCCUACGCAAGCAAGCCCACAUCGACACACAUUCACACACGCCCUUCAGCACCCCCUCCCAGCACCACGACCAUGGACGACGACUAUGAAGCGUACCACAGUCUGUUCUUGUCGCUGCUCGGACUCUGCCCGUCUAAGACUCCCAUCAAUGAAAAUGCUCCCGUCUUUGAUCCUGAACCGGUCAUUGCCCACUGCUUCAAGCAGUUCCAGCAGAAGGACUUCCGCCUGCCUCAGACCCGCCGGCGAAUCAUCAUGGUGCCUCGCAAGGAGGAUCAGACACCCCUUAAUCCUGCAUCCCAACCUCAGGCUCCCCCAAAGCCCAUCCCCAGCUUCAAAGUUCUGGAAGCUAGAGAUAUCCAAGAGCAGCCAGAGGACAGGAAGACCUGGCUGAGCCAGAGGUCGAAGCUGCGGCAGGAGCUAGAGUCCUUUGGUGAUGUAAAGAGGUGGCUGGAGAACAAGCCCAGCAUCACGCCUUCAGAGGCCAAGGUCUUACACAUGAUCCACGAGGAGCAGAGUGCCCAGCCAAAUGCCUCCCAGGCAACUACCAGGACCACCAGGAAGAAAGCCCCCAGGCUCUCCCGGCUGUCCCGCCAGAUGGUGCCCCAGCUCCAGCUGCCCGAGCCCCCUGCCCUGUCGGUCAUGUACUCCUACCUGCAUAGCCGCAAGAUCAAGAUCCUGGAGAUAUUUCACAAGGUGGGCCAGGGUGAGAACCAGAGAAUCACCAGGGAGGAGUUCAUCGCGGCUGUAAAGGCAGUCGGAGUCCCUCUGAAGAACCAAGAGGUGGAGGAUAUAGUGAUCUACCUCAGCUCUCUUGGGAAGCACAACACCAUCACCAUGGAUAUCCUGGCCAAUACCUACAAGCAGUGGUCUAUGGCUCAGCAAAGGAGCAGCCUGGCCACUGCAAGGGAGCAUUAUAUCUUGGCCAAGCACAGAGAUUCCCUGAAGGGUCCGCUCAAGAAGCAGGAGGUGGAUUCAGCCCCACAGCUUCCCAAAGUGGACCUACUGACGGUGCCUGCAGUCGACACGCAGAUGGAGACGCGGCCCAUGACCCUGGAGGAGAUGGAGGAAGUGGGCAAGCGGUACCGCGAGCGGCAGCGACAGCACAAGCUCACGAUCCCCUCCAUCCAGUACACGGAGCAAUGUCACCUGGUGCGCUGUGGGAAUCGGCACUUUGAUGAGCACUGCCUCCCGUCCACCAUCCACGGGGAUAUGAGGGAGCUCAUUGACUCGGCCCGCAGGCACAACUUUCUGGUCUACCUGCAAUGCUGGAAGCUCUGUAAGUCCUAUGGCCUCCCGCUGACAGAGGACAUCCUCAUGAAAGCCUUGCUGUACCCAGGAGACAAGAUCAUUUUCCAGAUGGACAAAGUGUGCCCCAUCCGGCAGCCGGGAGGCUACUACUCUGACUGGAAGGUCUUUUCUCCGAAUCUGGCUCUGCUCCGGUCCCAGGGCCCUGGCAAGUCUAAGAGGACUGACAAGAAAACGCCAAAGAAAAGCAAGAAAAUGCGCUUUAAGGAGUUUGAGGAAUUUACCAGGAAGCUGAAGGUGAAGAGGUCCAGUGGUCUGCAGCAAACACACCCCAAUUCCUUCUGGCCGGGUCAUCUUCUGGAUAAGCUGCAGCUCUACCUGCCCACUGUGGCCACAGACCGGAGCCUGGCGCUCUUCAGUUGUGUUCAACACCAGCCCCAUGUCUACCCAGCCACCUACCACCCUGACCACUGGUGGCCCCUUAGGAACAAGAACUACAUGACCCACGCCCAUUAUGAUGCCGCCAAGGUGUACUACAUCAACUAGAGCUAGCCAGGUGUUGCCGGACCCAGCCUUCCUGGGCCAGGGGCCAGUGCAGCCAGCGGCCCAGAGCCCAGACACAAGAGGAGUGUCAAAGAGUCAAACUAAAGAAAUCCUUUCAAAGAGGGAUGGACCGGGGGCCAGUUCCCUCUGGACUCAAAGUGUCCAGUGUCUCAGAGGGUAGAUGUGUCCAAGGAAUGACGUGCAGUUUUUGACUAUUUCCCUCCCCUGACCUCUGCCCUUUCUACAUAAAGCAGGUUGGAGUUUUUCUCAUUUCA